UUUUAAUGAAAUAAAGUUCUGAAGUGAAAUGGUUGAUUCUUUAUUUCUGGUUCCACCUUUUUCAAAACAGAACUCAGGAGUAUACUUCCAUCCUUGUGUGUCCUUCGACUCCCAUUCCCCCAGUUUUAAUUAGAAUCUCUGGAUAUGUUGCAAGGGCCUAAUAUAGGAAGGAAUAUAAAUUUAUAUGUGAUACACUUUUUUCUUUCCUCUCUUAGUUUGCAAUUUUAUUUCUUUCUUAGAUGAGAGGAAAGAUAGGAAUGAAGGUAGGACCAAGUGAAAUUCUUGUUGGCUAAGAGUGUGGCAAAUAGCAGAAGAACAUGAUGUGACAUCUUUUCUCUUCAAGCACAGGCUGUGGCCCAGAAUGAGAGAGAGAUGCUCCAUAAUGUCACAAGAGCUCUCCUUUCUCUUAGGCAUUGUUCUUUCCUUUAGACUUUCAUUUUGUUCAAGACAAAAGCAGACACCCUUGAGUAACGCCAGUAUUUCACAUUCCUACCUGUUUUAUUCUGCUGUCAGUAAUGAGUUGGCUGGAACGCGUGGGUUAUUCCCAGCAGCCAGUUUCUGUUUAUCCGUUAGGGGAUAGAAUAGUUUUAGAACAGCAAUUUUUUCAUAGUGGUGCCACUCGUUUCUUCCCAGCAUCCUGGGAUCAGUGGAAUCAAGGCCAACCUUUAGAGCAUAUGCAAUGAGUACAGCAUUUUAGAAGAUUGGACUGAGACCGGGGCUGGUGGGAUGUCUCUGCUGGGAGCCCUGGGAAGCUUGAACCCAGGUCCUGCAGAAUCUGCAGACUGUGGUUUGCUUCUUACCCUCUUUUCCAUAGAGAGUGGCAUACAUGGUUAUUGUUAUCUUAAGCAACUUUAGGAUACACAGCUUUGUGUUAGGUCAGAUAUGUUACAAAUAAGAUAGGUUGCAGCUUGCAUCCUCAAGGAAUUUUAUACAGGAAACAGGAAGAAAAGUGUGAUAGAAUAGUACAAGAUCAAUAUUGAUUUAAUGUGGAAAAAAAUUAUACAAAACUGUAAGUGUAUGGGGAAAAUAAUAUUUUACUCCCUUAAUUUCAUACCAGAAAAGAAAUCCCUUUUGUCCGUUUGGUCUGUUUGUCUAUACCUAUGUACAUAUGCACAAACACAUACAUGUAUAUGCAUAUACACACACAUCUACAUACAUACAUAACAAUGGGACUAUGUUGUACGUCAUUCUGCAUGUUAAUUUUUUCUUUUUUUUUUAGUAUAUGAUGAACAUUCUCUGCUGUCACUAUUCUAGAUUGACCUAUUGUUUGUGAUAGCUGCAUGGUAUUCCUAGUAUGUAUGUAUCACACUUUAUUUAACUGUUAUCUUUUUUUUUUUUUUUUCCUGGGACGGAGUCUCGCACUGUCGCCUGCGCUGGAGUGCAGUGGCAUGAUCUCAGCUAACUGCAACCUCUGCCUCCUGGAUUCAAGUGAUUCUUGUGCCUCAGCUACUGAGUAGCUGGGAUUAGAGGCACACGCCACCACACCCAGCUAAUUUUUGUAUUUUUAAUAGAGACAGAGUUUCACCAUGUUGGCCAGACUGGUCUCGAGCUCUUAACCUCAAGCUAUCCACCUGCCUCAGCCUUCCAAACUGCUGGGAUUACAGGUGUGAGCCACCGCGCCCCAGUUUAUUUAACUGUUAUCUUAUUGAUGAGUAUUAAAAAGAUGUUGAGUUUUUCACUGUGAAGUAAUGCUACAAUGAACAUUCUUAUCUGCAUGUUUAUGCUAGUGUUUUUAUCACGUAGAAUUCUAGACAAUAUUUAAAUUGUUUAAUAUUAAGAAAUACUGCCUACUCUUACUCCCAAAAUGCUGUACCAGUUCAUACUCCCACCAAUAGGCUAUAAUAGAGAUAUUGAUUGCAUAACAUAGUGGAAGUCUGUAGAAGAUUAUGGUUAUAAUAUGUUAUAAUUUGAUAGCACUUUGUAGUUUAUAAUUCACUUUCAUCUAUCUUAUUUAAUUCACCAACCUAUGGUGUGGUUUUAUAUCUGCAUCUUUGAGAUAAGGACAUUUGAGAGUCAGGAAAGUUCACUGACUUGCCUGAACAUCUUAGUUAAUGAAUGCAAGGGCCAAGACUAUUACCCAGAUAUUUUUUCUCUACUUUCGACAUCCUUAUAGUAAGAUAAUUUAGGAAAAGCUUGAGGUUGGCCAUAUUUAGAUGACAUUUUCUUAGCAUUUGUGAAAGUUGAUAGGUUUUAUGUAGUACUGGGUUACUAUGGAUUUGAAGGAAGAGAAAAAUGCAGAAAAUGAUUCAGAUCAAAUUGCAUAUAAAGAGAACAUACUUAGUGAACCAUGAAAGAAUUUUUUGGUUAUAUAUACACAUGGUAUCUAUAUCUAUCUGUAGAUAUAGAUACAUGCAUAUAUCUAUAUCUAAUCUGUAUAUCUUUAUAUCUAUCUAGGCAGCCCAGUGAAUUUUAACAUCAAGGCAGAAUUUUGUAUAAUGAGUUUCUUUCUAAGUUGUAAUGUGGUGCUCCUAUCUCUUUUGCAAGAUUUGUAGUCUGAGUCAUGGUAGAGAUAACAGGCAGUUAGACACAUUAGUUAACAUGCACUCUGAAUACAGGGUCAUUUGAAGGCCUAACUGGGGAGGCAAAGAUAGCAGGAUUCUCCUAGAGGGGUUAGAGAUGGAAGUUGUAGAAGAGAGGCUAUGAUUCUAAUGGGCUGGUAAAGCCAGUGUACUCCAGCUUGUAUGUGGAUCCAAGGAUGGUCUUUUAUUGGAGAUUAGAAAGGGAGGUUGGUUUUGAAAAUUUUCAGUGUAGAGAUACAGUCAAAAUAAUAUAAAGGAAGAGAAAAAGGAAAGGAGCAGAAAGGAAAGAGAAUAAAACCAUCUUGAAGAAUUAGAGAUGGCAGGACGAGAUAAAGAAAGAAGCUGGUACAGGAAGGGGAACAUCACGCUCUGGGGACUGUUGUGGGGUGGGGGGACGGGGGAGGGAUAGCUUUAGGAGAUAUACCUAAUGCUAAAUGAUGAGUUAAUGGGUGCAGCACACCAGCAUGGCACAUGUAUACAUAGGUAACUAACCUGCACAUUGUGCACAUGUACCCUAAAACUUAAAGUAUCAUAAUAAUAAAAUAAAAUAAAAAAAAGAAGCUGGCCCUGUUUAGUUGACUGGAGUUCAGUGUAGGUGUCCCACUUUUUUGCUCCUUUUCUCUGCAGUCCCAGUUUUGAUGAGGACUGCUUUGCAGAGUUUUAUGGAAGCCCUCAGCACUUCAGCCUGUGAAACUCUUCUGAAAAACAGCCAACAUUUAUAUUACUGCAGCAUCAGAAAAUCCUUUUGGGCACUGAAAGAAUUGGCCUGAAGAAAUCUUUCCUUUUACUUACUAAAUAUUCAGUUCUAUUGGGAUUGUAGAAUUUUCACUUUGUUUCAUGUGAAAUUGUGAUUAAAAGGUGGUCACUCCAGUUUUAGCAACCCCAUGGGAAAACUAAUCUCGUUGCUUUGGAGCUUUAUUGUAUUUUUACCAGAUAUUUGUACCAUCUGCAUUGGGAAACACUGAGCAAAUUCAGCACUGUUAAGAUUCUUUUUACUGAGUCUCAUUUUUUUAAAGAAAAAAAGUAUUUGUAUUUUUCAUGCAUAUUUAGAUUCCAUAUGUCAUAUAUUUUUGGCAGACCUAGACUUCUGUAAUCACGGUAUAGAGCCCUACAUUUACAUGAAUAUUCUGGUAAAAAAAUAUAGAUAUAAUCCUGAUUCAUUUCCACAUCAUUUCUAAAUUUAUUGUAAUUGCUUUUUAAAUUUAGCAAUAUGUUUUUGAAAACAUACAUGUGAUAUGUAAAAGAAAACAAAGUAUUAUGUUUUUCUAGUACUAGUGGCAUUUCUGUAUGUUGUAUUCUCUGUUUUACAGCAUAGCGUAGUGGCUAAGAACACACUUCCUGGGUUUAACUCCCAGCUUUGCCCAUUAUUAGUCAUGUGACCUUGGACAUGUUACUUGACCAUUCUGUGCAAUCGUUCCAUCAUCCUUAAAAUGGAUAUUAUAGCAGUAGUAAUGUCAUAGUUGCCGUGGAAUUUUUAAAGCUAACAUAUUCAAAGAGCUUAAGACAGUUCUUUGAUAUUAUACUUCCUAACAAAACUCAGGAGAUAAAAGGUUAUUCUUAAGAAUGCAGAUUGCCCCUUUGAAUACUGAAUAUCUUGAUAUGUCUAUUCCUUUAUGCUUCUGGAUACUUAAAAAACAAAAUUUUAAGAGUUUUGUUUUUGAGUUCCUACUGUUUUUAUUUGAAAUGUGUAACCACAGUGGAGGUGAUUAUUAGCUUUCUGAUUACUUUUCUCUGAUAUGUGUAGGAUAUUGUGUGAAAGGAAGGAGGCACAGGAUACUAAACAUAUUGAUAUUAUGCUUGAUGGCCUAAUUUGGUAAAAUUAUCCAGCAUAUGGAUAUAUUCUAAGAAAAACAAAGUCACCAAUCAUGGAAGUAGUCCAUGUAAUCCACUCGUCACCAAGUAGCUGGCUAGUGUCUCCAGGAGAUUAUGUCAUUUUCAAUAGGUUUAGUUUUGGUCCCUGUGUUGCCACAGUGAGUAUCCAGUGGCUAUAGCCAGAUUGAUCUGGGUGAGUGGAAGUCCAUGUUGCUGAGCACAUGUAUAAUCUCUGUCCCUUCUGCCAUGGCUAUGUUGUUCAUGAAUCCUUUAGGGAAGGACAGGAGUGACUAGAGAGAGAGGUUGAUUGAUCUCAAUAGAAUAGGUCAUCUUGUCUGCCUGAUUAUCAAGCUCUUCUUUUGAAAGUUGCUAUUUGGUGAGCAUUUACAUGACUAGCCAGUCAAACCAUUAGCUACUGUCUAUGAAUGAAUGUAGUUUUUCAUCUCUGGCAUGAAUUUGUCAAAAUGAACAACCAAGUAUACUAUUCAAAAUGUUGCCCACUGGGAGGUUUUCUCUGCUGUGCCCUUACGGGCUUCCAAGUGGGGCUGUAAUGCUACAACUCUUCACCCCUGUGUGGCACCAAUUUAUUGUGCAGAACCAUCUGCACAAUAAAUCAGGCCUUAAUUUUUUUCUUCUUUAGUUAACUGGUCAUAAGAAACUCCUCUCAGUGAGGUCACAGGUGAAGUUUAAAGAGAGGGUCAUUACAGCAAACAUAGGAGCUGUGGGAAUCUCAGCCACUUGCUCAUGUAACUGAACUGUGCCCUGAGCACCUGCCAGGUCUGAUUUCAUACAUACCCUUCUGUAUAAGGCUAAAAUGCUCCAUGCAAACCCAACUGUAUGGCUUCAGAAAGUCAGACAACACCAAGUUUAUGUGGAGCACUCAUGUUCCAUAGCUUUGUUCCAAAAUUCUAAAGAUCUGGUCUGACCUUUAAGGGGCCUGCCAAAUGCUAUACAGAAUCCCUAUGUGCCACAGACACCUAAAACACCAGUAAAUCUUUCGGCUCAGUGGCAGAGCAGCUUUCAUAGCAGCCCGGACCUGUUGUGGAGCCUUCUCUUAUUAUUACUGAUUACUCAAAUAUGGCAGCUUUUCAAGCUACUUGAUAAAUAGGUCAGAAUAACAUACCCAAAUGAGGUGCAUGUUGCCUCCAGAGUCCAGAAAAGCCAGCUAGAUGCUGUGUCUCUGUAUUAGUGGUAGGCAAGAGAGCUAUCACUUUGGAAGGGAUAUCUUGAAAUACUACUAAGACCCCUAGAAAAUUUAAAAGAUGGCAGGCCUCUGAAUUUUUUUAGGACUCUUUCUUCACUCUGUCGCACAUGUGUCUUACCAUGCAUAGGGUAUUUGCCACUUACUGUAUAGUCAGCAUGUAAUAGACAGCAUAACAUUCUAUGGACUAGAAGUACAACCAAGGUCCCUGUGAACGAGAUUAUGAUAGCGUGCUGGAGACUUGACAGAGCCCUGAGGUAGGAUAGUAGGGUAGGCAAAUGCUUCAAGUAGUCUUUGCUAACACAUAUAGAGAAAACCAGAAUUUGACAGAUCAAUAGCCAUGUACCAGAUGCCAGGAAAUAUGUUGAUUCGCUCCAUCAGUAAAACCACAUCUGGUACAGCAUCUGCACUCUUCAAAAUCCAUCUGUUUUGUACAAAGCCAAAGAGACAACUUGAAUAGAGAUAUGGCAGAAAUGAUCACCUUCUUCUUGCAAGUCCUUGAUGGUGACUCUAAUCUUUGCAAUCUCUGCAGGAAUGAAAUGUUGCUUUUGGUUUACUUUCAUAGGUAGAAAUAGAUAGUUCUAAGGGUUUGCAGUUAACCUUUCCUACCAUUAUACCCUUGCUCCACAGAUUAGAGAACCAGUGAGAGAAUCUGCUGAGUUUGUCUGUUCUAACUCAGCAUUUCAAAACUGGUAGAAUAACCAUGGCAUGAGUUCUGGGAUGAGUGGGAGUUGUAAUGAGCCCAAACUUCAUUAAUCAUGUGAUUUCCAUAAACUCCUGCUCUGAAUAGAAUCAGUACUGUAGAAUAUGAUACUGACAUGGUUGGGCUGUUUGUCCCCUCCAGAUCUCAUGUUGAAAUGGAAUCCCCAGUGUUGGAGGUUUGGGCCUGGUUAGAGGUAUUUGAGUCAUGGGGUGGAUCCCUCAUGAAUGCCUUGAUGCUGUCCUCCCCGUAGUGAGUGAGUUUUUGCACUGAGUUCACACAAGAUCUGGUUUUUUAAAAGGGUAUGGCACCAACCCCUCUCGCUCUCUUGUUCCUGCUCUCACCCUUCACCUUCCACCAUGAUUGUAAGCCUCCUGAAACCUCUCCAGGAGCAGAUGCUGGCACCAUGCUUCUCAUACAGCCUGCAGAAUUGUGAGACAAAAUAAACCUCUGUUCCUUAUAAAUUGCACAGCCUCAUCCUUUGGGAAAAAAGAAUGUAUGUGUGUGUGUGUAUGUAUAUUUAAAUGCCAACAAAUUUAUAAGAAAAAGAUAACCCAGCUGAAAGAUGAGCAAAGGACUUGAACAAAAACUUCAACAAAAAAUAUCCAAACAGCCAAAACAAAACAAACAAAAAAAUGGAGAAUAAAUAUGUAAGUUAUUUAUUAAUUUUAGGAUUUCUAAAAGUUAAACAAGAACGGAAAAUAUUCUACUGUUGGCUUAUCAGUAAAUAUACUAUUUACAUAACUACAUUAAUACACUACUGUAAUUCAGAAGUUUCAAAUAAAGAUUUUGAUAGUACAAAGGGAAGAGAAAUUAGUUGGAAAUGCUGUGACAGCUAAAUCUACAUCUAUACUUACAGGAAAUCAGGAGUUAAUAUAUUUAAGUGAUAAACCAAAAAGUAAUUUCUUCAUGUUAUUUAGAUAUAUAAAGAAUAAAUAUAUGAAAAAACCUUUAAAAUAAUUAAGAAUGAGUACCUCUAAAAACAGGAAUGGGGUGGUGAAGAUUGGGACAGGGUUUGAUGAUCACCUUAAAACUUAUCUAAUUAUUUUUAAAAUUAUGUGCAUAUUUUAUGAAUAUUAAAAUGAGUAAACAAAAAAUUGAUCCCACAAAACAGUGCAAAUGAAUUUAGUUAUCUAAAUAUUUAUCAGAAUGUGUGCAAAGCAUAGUGGUCGUAGGGAACAAUGGGAUUAAUAAAAUCAAUGGCUGCCUUCUAGGAGAAUAUAGCCUUUUCAGAGAAUAAAACAAGUACUUAAAGCACUCCAAAGAUCACUUGAGCUUGGGAGGUCAAGGCUACAGUGAGCUGUGAUUGUGCCACCACACUCCAGCCUGGGUGAUAGAGUGAGAUCCUGUCUCAAAAAAAUAAAAUAAAGCACUCCAGUGGCAGGUAAGACUAAGGAAAGAGGACCAAGAGAAUACUACAACCGCUACUGACCAUUCUAGCCACUGAAGCCCAAUAAAUAUGACAUUCUGGCACACUCCAAAUAUAAAACACUCCACUUAUAUCAUUAACCUGAUAGCCCAGCAUUGUUUCUGUAGAUGGAAUAAGAGAGAAUCAUAAAUCCAGUCACUUCUACCAUACGCGAGUUUUACAAGUACACAUACAUGUGGUGUGUUUGUAUAAACAUGUGUAUUAUGUAUGCAUAUAUCAUGUGCACACAUUCACACAUAAUUUAAAAUUUUUCUCACUUGGAAGAUUUGUUAAACAUUUCCAACAAAUGGCAAAUAAAGACUAGUCGAGAUUGGAUUUAACAUUAAGACUCCUGUGUAAAUGUUACCAACCUACGCUGUCUGUUGCUCUCAUGCUGUUACUGUCCUAUUUCAUUUGGAAAUACAAAUUGUAAGUGUGAAACUUUUUAACCUAUUCUUACAUAAAAUUCAAAGAAACUUCAGGUGACAAUGAUAUUUGAUGAGAAAUGCUUAGAGGAAAGAAUCUUUUAAUGUAGUUACUGUGAGCAUUCAAGAGCACUGCUUUGGUUAUUAUACUUCAUAAGAAAAGGAAGAAGGCCAGGGAAUAUUUACAUUCCAAUGAGCCAGGAGUGAAGUGAAUGACGACCACUGUACAGAUACUGAGGCAAAGGCAUUAUUAAGUCUGUUCAUGCUAUGUUCCUUAGUAUUUUAAAUUGAAGUUAUUUUCCUUAAUGUUUAACUACAAAAAUGCUUUUGUUUAAUUUCUUUGUUAAACUCUUUAUUUCUUAGAGAAAUUGACAAUUUAUAUCUAAUAGGCACUGAAAAGUUGAUUAGAAUCUCUGUGUUCAUGGGCUGGUUUGACAGUGGGUAGGCUUCCAUAUACAGGUGACUGGUCACCAAGCUGGCAUUGUUCUUGGGCUACCAUCAGAUGUUAGUAUCUAGAGGUUUUUCCUCUGUGGCAGUUUAGUUACAGCCUUUGAGUCUUCUGCAUGGGCAAUAUGUGCCUGGCUUCUGGCAGUCUGAGAGCAGGAUGGCAAAAGGAGCUAGGUUCUCAAAUUGAAUAUGCAUUCACUCAGUCCCCCUGUUUUCAGCCUUGCACUAAUAUUUUCGAGUGUGGUGCUUGUCAGGUUCAGUUGUGCCACAGAGUUGGGCUACUGAAAUGGAGAUACGUGCUUUCAUGUGAUUGUUCAGAGAGGAGAACUAGGUGUGGAGUGGGGUUCCAGUGUCUGAUUUUCAGUCAGUUUUCCAGUUUUCAGCUCUGCCUAUAUACUCUGUGGUAAUUGGCAUCCAGAGAUUCUCUGGGCAUCUACAGGAUUGUUUCAGUUUCUUCAAAGCAUAUUUCCCUGGAAGUAUUGAGAAUAAAUUGUUCUCUGUUCUGGUUUCUUAAGUCAGUUACUACAACACCAUUUGCUUUUUUUGCCUUAAAACAUUAAAAAACAUCCUGGCAAACCAGGUGAAACCCCGUCUUUACUAAAAAUACAAAAAAAAAAAAAAUUAGCUGGGCAUGGUGGCAGGUGCUUGUAGUCCCAGAUACUCGUGAGGCUGAGGCAGAAGAAUGACGUGAACCCAGGAGGUGGAGCUUGUAGUGAGCCAAGACUGUGCCACUGCACUCCAGCCUGGGUGACAGAGCGAGACUCUGUCUCAAAAAAAAAAAAAAAAAUUAGAAAAAAUUUUUUAUCUACUGAUGUGUUUUUCAUUUAUACCUCUUGUCCUUUUGGUUUAUAUACUUUGUUUAAAAAAUCCCUUUACUGUCAUUUCAGUGUAAUUUUCGGGAUGUGGACUGUGGUCAGUCUUCAUUUUUUACGAGAAAUUUAGAAACCAUUUAUUUGCUCACCAUUUUCCUUUUAGUACCUGGCAUGUAGUAGGUUCUUAAAUAGAUAUUUGAUGAAAUAUUGAAUGAAUUGUUAGAAGUUUUUAUAGUUGUGGGAAGCUUUUAUGGUAGAAAGAUACAAUGACUAUGCAAAUAUAACAAGUUAAAAGUCAUCUUUUAAAUUAUGGUUUUACUUUGGCUUCAUCCCAUUUUUUGUUUUUGUUCCUUAACAUGGUCAAGGAAAUGAAAUAUUUUAAACAGUGUGGUAGUACAGGAUGGAUAUAUGUUAGUUUACUUUGUCAAACACAAUUUUAGCUGUCACAUUAGGCUUAAGAUACACAUUUGUCUAUUUAUAAUUUUUCUAGAGAAAUUACCUCUACCUCUAUGGAGGUAGACUUGUAUUGAGGUUAAUUUACAAUUAAGCACAGCCUUUAGUCUUAAUUAUAUGUAUAUUUAGGGUACUUCUAUAGAGGCUGAUGGUGAUUAUGGUGUAAAAUCUUCCAACUACCACUGCUCUCUUCCCACUGGCCCCUUUGUGGUUAAUAAAGUUCAAGAGCAGCUGGCUUAGUGUGGCAUCUUAUCCAGGUAUGUUUUGUAUUACAAAGUGAAUAUGUGAGGAUAGAUAAAAUCUAGUAAGGGCAAAGAAAUUAAACCGUAGAAGUGAACGCAAGUAGUAAAGUUGAUAUUUUGAAUGAAUAGAUCAGGAUUCUUCUUUUUAUAAAGGCAGCCCUGGACAAAAAAAGAUGGGAUUGUAGAGCUAUAGGUAUGUAGAGAGUCCCUGAUUUGGCUACAUUGCUGGAUCUUGGGUCUUAGAAAUGUGAUAUCCCUACCCAUCAUGCAUUAGUAAAUGAAUGAAUGAAAUUUUGACAGUGACCCUUAAAAUCAAUGACUAGGCUGGGUGCAGUGGCUCACGCCUGUAAUCCCAACACUUUGGGAAGCUGAGGCGGGUGGAUCACCUGAGGUCAGGAGUUCGAGACCAGCCUGACCAACAUGGAGAAACCCCGUCUCUACUAAAAAUACAAAAUUAGCCGGGCUUGGUGGUGCAUACCUGUAAUCCCAGCUACUCGGGAGGCUGAGGUAGGAGAACCGCUUGAACCCAGGAGGCGGAGGUUGCGGUGAGCUGAGAUCGCACCAUCUGGGCAACAAGAGUGAGACUCUGUCUGGAAAAAAAAAAAAAAAAUCAAUGACUGAUUCUAAGUCGAAAUAAUGAGUAAACUGCAGUUUGUUUUAAACUGCUGUACAUGUAUGUUUUCCCAGUCUCUUAAGAGCUUAUUAAAGGAAUCUAGCCAGAAAUUCAGAGACUUCUUUCUAACUAUAAAGAGGUUACCUCUCCAGUAAAGACCUACGGAAGGAAAAACCCAUACCACAAAAUGUGUAAGACAGCAGAUAAAGAAAGUCCCUUACAGAAAACUCUGGAGUUACAGAAAUCUGGGCAAAAGGACUCUUGUGGAAGAUGGAACUCAUUGUCCAUUUUCCAGAAUGUAUUUCCAAGCCCAUCAAUGGGACCUGAUACUGCUGUUCUGUGUUGAAAUGCUUGAAGAACUCCUGCAUCUCUGCUUGCAUCUUCCAUCCUACUGAAACCAUGGUCUUCUCGGCAGUGUUGACUGCGUUCCAUACCGGGACAUCCAACACAACAUUUGUCGUGUAUGAAAACACCUACAUGAAUAUUACACUCCCUCCACCAUUCCAGCAUCCUGACCUCAGUCCAUUGCUUAGAUAUAGUUUUGAAACCAUGGCUCCCACUGGUUUGAGUUCCUUGACCGUGAAUAGUACAGCUGUGCCCACAACACCAGCAGCAUUUAAGAGCCUAAACUUGCCUCUUCAGAUCACCCUUUCUGCUAUAAUGAUAUUCAUUCUGUUUGUGUCUUUUCUUGGGAACUUGGUUGUUUGCCUCAUGGUUUACCAAAAAGCUGCCAUGAGGUCUGCAAUUAACAUCCUCCUUGCCAGCCUAGCUUUUGCAGACAUGUUGCUUGCAGUGCUGAACAUGCCCUUUGCCCUGGUAACUAUUCUUACUACCCGAUGGAUUUUUGGGAAAUUCUUCUGUAGGGUAUCUGCUAUGUUUUUCUGGUUAUUUGUGAUAGAAGGAGUAGCCAUCCUGCUCAUCAUUAGCAUAGAUAGGUUCCUUAUUAUAGUCCAGAGGCAGGAUAAGCUAAACCCAUAUAGAGCUAAGGUUCUGAUUGCAGUUUCUUGGGCAACUUCCUUUUGUGUAGCUUUUCCUUUAGCCGUAGGAAACCCCGACCUGCAGAUACCUUCCCGAGCUCCCCAGUGUGUGUUUGGGUACACAACCAAUCCAGGCUACCAGGCUUAUGUGAUUUUGAUUUCUCUCAUUUCUUUCUUCAUACCCUUCCUGGUAAUACUGUACUCAUUUAUGGGCAUACUCAACACCCUUCGGCACAAUGCCUUGAGGAUCCAUAGCUACCCUGAAGGUAUAUGCCUCAGCCAGGCCAGCAAACUGGGUCUCAUGAGUCUGCAGAGACCUUUCCAGAUGAGCAUUGACAUGGGCUUUAAAACACGUGCCUUCACCACUAUUUUGAUUCUCUUUGCUGUCUUCAUUGUCUGCUGGGCCCCAUUCACCACUUACAGCCUUGUGGCAACAUUCAGUAAGCACUUUUACUAUCAGCACAACUUUUUUGAGAUUAGCACCUGGCUACUGUGGCUCUGCUACCUCAAGUCUGCAUUGAAUCCGCUGAUCUACUACUGGAGGAUUAAGAAAUUCCAUGAUGCUUGCCUGGACAUGAUGCCUAAGUCCUUCAAGUUUUUGCCGCAGCUCCCUGGUCACACAAAGCGACGGAUACGUCCUAGUGCUGUCUAUGUGUGUGGGGAACAUCGGACGGUGGUGUGAAUAUUGGAACUGGCUGACAUUUUGGGUGAUGCUUGUUCUUUAUUGACAUUGAAUUCUCUUUCUCAUAGCCUCUCCACUUUAUUUUUUUUUAUAGGGUUUGUGUAUGUAUGUGUGUGAGCAGUGUAAAGAAAGAAUGGUAAUUAUAGUUCUGUUACCAAGAAUAAAUAAUAGGAAAGUGAUUACAAAUAUUACCUCCAGGGUUCAAUAGAAAUCCUCAAUUUAGGGUGAGGAGACUUUUUUUUGGUUUUGGGGUUUUUCCUUGAUUGAUUUUGUUUUCAUAGUGGGAAUCAGGAUUGUGCUUUAUUGAGCCUGCAGUUACAUUGAAUUGUAGGUGUUUCGUGUGCUGCUAAGGUAUGCUUAUUUGAGUUUAUCAAGACUUUUUUUUUCUGGAAGACACUGCUGCUUUUACCAUCACAUUGGAGCCAAACAUCUCAAUCAAUAUAUAUUUAGUUUUAUUUUAAAAACUAACCCAGGAAGGUUAGCGACAUUUUAAGGGUCAUUACUAUUUACUUUGGUGCACUUUAAGAGAUAAUGUACAAAUUAAUUCAGUCUUAUUUUUCAGAAUUGUUUUUAUACAUGAUAUGUGCUUUAGGAAAUGUGCAUUAUCAUUUAUGGGAAGAUAGUUUUAAGAAAUGUUUUAUCUGCAUGUACAGUUGUAAAAGAGAACAUAAAAUGUAGAUACUUUUCUAAGCACAAUAGCAACUCUUCAAGCAAUAGCGCAAAAUCUAGGAGACAGGAUCCUUGCAAAUUUAAAAGGUGAAUGUAGUGAGGGGGAUGGCAAGUGGCUGGUACAGGCUGUGGUGAUUCCUUUUACUCAAGGGUUUUUGUGGAGUAUAGGGAGAAGGGGUUGAUAUUUAUGGACACCUAUGUGUCAGGCACUGUGCAUCAUUUUAUCCUUACAGGAUGUUGUGAGGUAGGUAUUAUUGUUUUCAUUUUUACAGGUGAAGAAAGCAGGUCUCAGAGGGACUAAAAUCCUGCCCAAGGUUAGUGGUAGAGCUGGGAUCCAAAAAUCUGUCAGAAUCCUGAGACUGCGCUGUUCCACUGUGCCACGCAGACAGUUCAUUCAGUUUAGAUGUCACAUAGUCAAGAGGGAACUCUAUGCAUCCUUUAAUUUUUUAGACUAUGAUAUUCUUUUUAAAAAUUAGCCUUUAUUUUCUAACUACCAAAAGAAAUAUGAAAGCAUUACAGAAACACUGGAAAAUAGAAAAGAAAAAAUAAAAUCACUUACAACCACUUUUUGUUUUUUGGAGUCUCGCUUUGCCACCCAGGCUGGAGUGCAGUGGUGUGAUCAUGGCUCAUUGUAGCCUCAACCUCCCAGGCUCAGGUAAUCCUCCUGUCUCAGCCUCCUGAAUAGCUGGAACCACACACACACACGCACACACAGGUGUGUGCCACCACACCCAGCUAUUUUUUUGUAUUUUCUUUUGUAAAGACAAGGUUUCACCAUGUUGCCCAGGCUGGUCUCAGAGUCCUGAGCUCAAACGAUCUGCCUGCCUUGGCCUCCCAAAAUGUUGGGAUUACAGGCAUGAGCCACCACAUCUGACCUACAACCACUUUUUAAUGUGAGACUUAAAAAUCUUAGAUAAAUAAGGCUGUGAAGCAAAACCAGUGAUUUUUUUUUUUGUUUUUGAUUUGCAAAACAAGUGACUGACAAUUAUUGAGAAAUUAAAGAUAGCUAUGUGUAGGUCUUGCCCCUGCGGGUUUGGAGGUUUCCAGUUGUCCAUCUGUGUUAGUUGUAAGUGUUCUGGGCAGAAUAGUAUUGUUGCCCCAAUGCUUGCCCUAGCAGAGCUGGAGUUUGUGAACGUGCUCAGAUGUGUGUCUCCUACAAAGAAGGGAAAAUGAACCCUCGUCUGAGCCUAGAACAAGUUUUAAUAGGGCAUGUCUGACAUUUCAAAUUGUUUUUCUCUUGCUGACAGUCUGCCCCCAGGUGCAUCUAGGGCCUUGGUCAGCUUCUCUGUUACCAGUGGCUCACUUUAUAAAACAGCCCACAGGGAUAAGGGCUGAAAAUAUAGCCACUUGGCUACAUCAUUGACUAAUUAAGUAAGUUAACUGUGGAUUUAUAGCAUCUUUUCAGGAUGUUAGUGUUUUGUGAGCCAGUGGAAAAAAUAAGCUUCUAUUUCUUCAUUUGUAAAACCAGAGAGUUGGAUUAGAUGAAUCUCUAACGUCCUGUCCAGCUCAAAUGUGCUUUCCUCUAUACUAGGGUAUAGAUUUUUGAAGAGCCUAGCUGACUUCAGCAUCACCUCACCCUUUGGUCUCCAGUAUUACUUCUUUACAUUUUACUUCAUUAGCUAUUUCUUAAUAUUAAAUGUCUGAAGAGUGUGGCACUGUAUCAGGAGUUGGGGCAUUGAAAGGUUGAAGACAUCAUGAAAUAUCUGGGAAACUCUGCUCUUAAGGAAAUUGCACCGAUGUUGGAACUCAUUGUCCAGUUAAAGAGCUCUUUGGGGACUCAAGCAUAUUAUUCAACAUGUUGUUUUGGGAUUAUCUUCAAAUGAUAGUCACCUACCUCUUUCAUUUCUAAUUUUUAUUCACAGGUAAAAUUGUUUUUGUCCAUAGGGAUUUUAUAGGACAUAAGCACUGUAGUAGAUACUAGUAGCAUUUUGAAGUGUAUUAUGCUCUCCAUUUUCCAUAUAAACUAGAUUUCAAGCAGAUAUUGAUAAGGACAUUUUUUAUUAGACUUUUCUCUGAGGAAAGUCAGCAUGAUCUGUAUUCAUCUUACAUAUUGAUAGGUCAUGAAGACUCCUUUUUGGCUGGAGGUGAAACUGAGCUUUGUUUUCUUUGUUCCUGUUUUAUGGGCAGUCUUUAGGUACUUUCAUGCUGCUUAAUAGGCAGUGCCUCAUUUGGUGAGAGCUCUGGAGUGCCUGCCGAGACGCUCCCUGUUUGUGAACAAAGAUUAUGAAGGGGUCUUUGUGAGAAUUCAGCAGCAACACUGAACAGCAGUUCUUUUUACACUGGAUUAUCUUGAUCUGAUGAGAGUUUACAAAUCAUUUUGAACAUUUUUAUUAUGUAUACAUUGUGAAAGCUUUAAAAAUAAGUACUAUGGAGCACCUUUGAGAAACGUAGGUGCAAAAUCAUAUGUUGCCUAUUCCCCCAUAUUUUCUUGAGGCAGGGAAAGAUACCACUACUAAUUCUCACUGCUUACAGGCAUAAUCAGAAAUGGUUUUUUGUUUGCCUGUUUUUCCUUCUGGCUAGUAAGAAGCGUAAAAGAGAUAAUGAAAUAUUUGUGGUCAAAAGAAAGAUGCAAGGGAAAUUCCAAAUAGUAUGGAGUAACAUUAUUUAAACUUUAAUACAUGUUUAAGCAUCCCCAAGGGAGCUUGUUAACAGUACAGAUUCCUGGGCCUCCAGAGGGUCUGUGGUUGAGCCCAGGAAUGUGCAUUUUUAUUUUAUUGAGCACUCUGCCUGACUCUGGCUCAGGUAGUCCCUGGGAAACUCUUCAGGAAACAUUCCUGUAGAAAAUAUAUCUAUUUAAAUAUCAUCUGUUUUAUCCCACAAUGUUUGUUUCGUGUUGCAAGCCAUUAUCUUCUAGGCAUGGGUAAUCCACAUUGAGAGGAAAAUCCACACAACAUUGUGCCUGAUUUGCUGCCACCUGUGUUUGUGCUGGAUCUUGCCAGUGUUAGCUUUAUUUUCUUUCAACUGGCAAAAUUCUGAUAAAGCAUAUAGCUUCACAGUAGAGCAAAAUGGGUGACUUAAUUGAAAGUCAUGACUUUCAGCAGUCUAAUUAUGCUCAUAUUUUAUUUUCUUAUAGAGAGCUGUCUUUAUUGUGUGUAAUUCCCGGAAGAAUGUAAAGAUUUAUCUAAUUCCUAUUGCUCUGCCAGUUGUGUUCAAUGCAAGCAUUGAAGUAAAAUAAAAAUAACCUUUUUAAUAUGUGUAUUUCUGUUGCCCACAAAGAUAUUUAAUUUUUUUCUUGAUCUUUGUUUUUGUUUAUGUGAAAAUAUUUACAUAUGUAUCAUUUCUGUAUAUAUCACAGAAAAGUUUUCACUUGCUUGACAUUUUAUUCUACAAUGAUUUUUAGUUUAAGUUUAAAGAAUGGCUACAUUCAGAUUUAUUUUCACAACUAUAGUCCUGCUAAACUGCCUUCAUUGAAAACUCAGUUUUUAUGAUAAAAAAUAUCAAAGCACAAGUUUGUUAUUGGAGGUAAAUUAUACAUUUCUUAGAUAUCUAUUGGUACUAGACCUUUGUAAUUAAAAUUAAUUUAUUUUACAAUAGUAACUGACCUGUAUGGAAAAAAAAACAACCUUGAAUUAUGGGUUCUAAUAUUUAAAUAUCGAAAAAUAUGGUUAUUUGUGCAUAUUCUUAUUACAACCAAGAAAAGAACUCCUGAUAAGAAAAUAAAUAAAUAUUUAACAUUUC